AUGCUACUCCCGGGCCAUUUCUGGACAACAGCUGCUAUUUUCACUUGAGCCGAAGUUAAUUUCUCGGGGAGUUCUCGGGCGCGCACAGGCAGCUCGGUUUGCCCUGCGAUUGAGCUGCGGGUCGCGGCCGGCGCCGGCCUCUCCAAUGGCAAAUGUGUGUGGCUGGAGGCGAGCGCGAGGCUUUCGGCAAAGGCAGUCGAGUGUUUGCAGACCGGGGCGAGUCCUGUGAAAGCAGAUAAAAGAAAACAUUUAUUAACGUGUCAUUACGAGGGGAGCGCCCGGCCGGGGCUGUCGCACUCCCCGCGGAACAUUUGGCUCCCUCCAGCUCCGAGAGAGGAGAAGAAGAAAGCGGAAAAGAGGCAGAUUCACGUCGUUUCCAGCCAAGUGGACCUGAUCGAUGGCCCUCCUGAAUUUAUCACGAUAUUUGAUUUAUUAGCGAUGCCCCCUGGUUUGUGUGUUACGCACACACACGUGCACACAAGGCUCUGGCUCGCUUCCCUCCCUCGUUUCCAGCUCCUGGGCGAAUCCCACAUCUGUUUCAACUCUCCGCCGAGGGCGAGCAGGAGCGAGAGUGUGUCGAAUCUGCGAGUGAAGAGGGACGAGGGAAAAGAAACAAAGCCACAGACGCAACUUGAGACUCCCGCAUCCCAAAAGAAGCACCAGAUCAGCAAAAAAAGAAGAUGGGCCCCCCGAGCCUCGUGCUGUGCUUGCUGUCCGCAACUGUGUUCUCCCUGCUGGGUGGAAGCUCGGCCUUCCUGUCGCACCACCGCCUGAAAGGCAGGUUUCAGAGGGACCGCAGGAACAUCCGCCCCAACAUCAUCCUGGUGCUGACGGACGACCAGGAUGUGGAGCUGGGUUCCAUGCAGGUGAUGAACAAGACCCGGCGCAUCAUGGAGCAGGGCGGGGCGCACUUCAUCAACGCCUUCGUGACCACACCCAUGUGCUGCCCCUCACGCUCCUCCAUCCUCACUGGCAAGUACGUCCACAACCACAACACCUACACCAACAAUGAGAACUGCUCCUCGCCCUCCUGGCAGGCACAGCACGAGAGCCGCACCUUUGCCGUGUACCUCAAUAGCACUGGCUACCGGACAGCUUUCUUCGGGAAGUAUCUUAAUGAAUACAACGGCUCCUACGUGCCACCCGGCUGGAAGGAGUGGGUCGGACUCCUUAAAAACUCCCGCUUUUAUAACUACACGCUGUGUCGGAACGGGGUGAAAGAGAAGCACGGCUCCGACUACUCCAAGGAUUACCUCACAGACCUCAUCACCAAUGACAGCGUGAGCUUCUUCCGCACGUCCAAGAAGAUGUACCCGCACAGGCCAGUCCUCAUGGUCAUCAGCCAUGCAGCCCCCCACGGCCCUGAGGAUUCAGCCCCACAAUAUUCACGCCUCUUCCCAAACGCAUCUCAGCACAUCACGCCGAGCUACAACUACGCGCCCAACCCGGACAAACACUGGAUCAUGCGCUACACGGGGCCCAUGAAGCCCAUCCACAUGGAAUUCACCAACAUGCUCCAGCGGAAGCGCUUGCAGACCCUCAUGUCGGUGGACGACUCCAUGGAGACGAUUUACAACAUGCUGGUUGAGACGGGCGAGCUGGACAACACGUACAUCGUAUACACCGCCGACCACGGUUACCACAUCGGCCAGUUUGGCCUGGUGAAAGGGAAAUCCAUGCCAUAUGAGUUUGACAUCAGGGUCCCGUUCUACGUGAGGGGCCCCAACGUGGAAGCCGGCUGUCUGAAUCCCCACAUCGUCCUCAACAUUGACCUGGCCCCCACCAUCCUGGACAUUGCAGGCCUGGACAUACCUGCGGAUAUGGACGGGAAAUCCAUCCUCAAGCUGCUGGACACGGAGCGGCCGGUGAAUCGGUUUCACUUGAAAAAGAAGAUGAGGGUCUGGCGGGACUCCUUCUUGGUGGAGAGAGGCAAGCUGCUACACAAGAGAGACAAUGACAAGGUGGACGCCCAGGAGGAGAACUUUCUGCCCAAGUACCAGCGUGUGAAGGACCUGUGUCAGCGUGCUGAGUACCAGACGGCGUGUGAGCAGCUGGGACAGAAGUGGCAGUGUGUGGAGGACGCCACGGGGAAGCUGAAGCUGCAUAAGUGCAAGGGCCCCAUGCGGCUGGGCGGCAGCAGAGCCCUCUCCAACCUCGUGCCCAAGUACUACGGGCAGGGCAGCGAGGCCUGCACCUGUGACAGCGGGGACUACAAGCUCAGCCUGGCCGGACGCCGGAAAAAACUCUUCAAGAAGAAGUACAAGGCCAGCUAUGUCCGCAGUCGCUCCAUCCGCUCAGUGGCCAUCGAGGUGGACGGCAGGGUGUACCACGUAGGCCUGGGUGAUGCCGCCCAGCCCCGAAACCUCACCAAGCGGCACUGGCCAGGGGCCCCUGAGGACCAAGAUGACAAGGAUGGUGGGGACUUCAGUGGCACUGGAGGCCUUCCCGACUAUUCAGCCGCCAACCCCAUUAAAGUGACACAUCGCAGGUGCUACAUCCUAGAGAACGACACAGUCCAGUGUGACCUGGACCUGUACAAGUCCCUGCAGGCCUGGAAAGACCACAAGCUGCACAUCGACCACGAGAUUGAAACCCUGCAGAACAAAAUUAAGAACCUGAGGGAAGUCCGAGGUCACCUGAAGAAAAAGCGGCCAGAAGAAUGUGACUGUCACAAAAUCAGCUACCACACCCAGCACAAAGGCCGCCUCAAGCACAGAGGCUCCAGUCUGCAUCCUUUCAGGAAGGGCCUGCAAGAGAAGGACAAGGUGUGGCUGUUGCGGGAGCAGAAGCGCAAGAAGAAACUCCGCAAGCUGCUCAAGCGCCUGCAGAACAACGACACGUGCAGCAUGCCAGGCCUCACGUGCUUCACCCACGACAACCAGCACUGGCAGACGGCGCCUUUCUGGACACUGGGGCCUUUCUGUGCCUGCACCAGCGCCAACAAUAACACGUACUGGUGCAUGAGGACCAUCAAUGAGACUCACAAUUUCCUCUUCUGUGAAUUUGCAACUGGCUUCCUAGAGUACUUUGAUCUCAACACAGACCCCUACCAGCUGAUGAAUGCAGUGAACACACUGGACAGGGAUGUCCUCAACCAGCUACACGUACAGCUCAUGGAGCUGAGGAGCUGCAAGGGUUACAAGCAGUGUAACCCCCGGACUCGAAACAUGGACCUGGGACUUAAAGAUGGAGGAAGCUAUGAGCAAUACAGGCAGUUUCAGCGUCGAAAGUGGCCAGAAAUGAAGAGACCUUCUUCCAAAUCACUGGGACAACUGUGGGAAGGCUGGGAAGGUUAAGAAACAACAGAGGUGGACCUCCAAAAACAUAGAGGCAUCACCUGACUGCACAGGCAAUGAAAAACCAUGUGGGUGAUUUCCAGCAGACCUGUGGUAUUGGCCAGGAGGCCUGAGAAAGCAAGCACGCACUCUCAGUCAACAUGACAGAUUCUGGAGGAUAACCAGCAGGAGCAGAGAUAACUUCAGGAAGUCCAUUUUUGCCCCUGCUUUUGCUUUGGAUUAUACCUCACCAGCUGCACAAAAUGCAUUUUUUCGUAUCAAAAAGUCACCACUAACCCUCCCCCAGAAGCUCACAAAGGAAAACGGAGAGAGCGAGCGAGAGAGAUUUCCUUGGAAAUUUCUCCCAAGGGCGAAAGUCAUUGGAAUUUUUAAAUCAUAGGGGAAAAGCAGUCCUGUUCUAAAUCCUCUUAUUCUUUUGGUUUGUCACAAAGAAGGAACUAAGAAGCAGGACAGAGGCAACGUGGAGAGGCUGAAAACAGUGCAGAGACGUUUGACAAUGAGUCAGUAGCACAAAAGAGAUGACAUUUACCUAGCACUAUAAACCCUGGUUGCCUCUGAAGAAACUGCCUUCAUUGUAUAUAUGUGACUAUUUACAUGUAAUCAACAUGGGAACUUUUAGGGGAACCUAAUAAGAAAUCCCAAUUUUCAGGAGUGGUGGUGUCAAUAAACGCUCUGUGGCCAGUGUAAAAGAAAAUCCCUCGCAGUUGUGGACAUUUCUGUUCCUGUCCAGAUACCAUUUCUCCUAGUAUUUCUUUGUUAUGUCCCAGAACUGAUGUUUUUUUUUUAAGGUACUGAAAAGAAAUGAAGUUGAUGUAUGUCCCAAGUUUUGAUGAAACUGUAUUUGUAAAAAAAAUUUUGUAGUUUAAGUAUUGUCAUACAGUGUUCAAAACCCCAGCCAAUGACCAGCAGUUGGUAUGAAGAACCUUUGACAUUUUGUAAAAGGCCAUUUCUUGGGA